CGGGCAGGUUUGUGGCAACCUGGGGUGGCAUCAUGUGCCCAGCUGCUCCCUUCUGGUCUCAGGCUCCAGAACUGCAGAUCCUAUUGUCUGCCUGCACGCGUGUGGGGCUGGCCUGGGGUGCCAGGAGGCAGGCACCGCGUGUGUCUGUCUUGCCAGGCUGUGUUUAAGAAAGGUGACACAGCAGAUAGGCCGGAUGAGGAGCCUCUGACCUGCAGUCCUGGGCCUGGUCUCAGAGAGGCUGCCCUGCAGAUGUCGAACCCCGGGCAGCCAUCCUGCAUGUCCAGUGGAGGCUCCUUUCUGGGUCCAGAUUGGGCCAUGAAUAGGCCAUGUUCUUCAAAGGACUGCUUUCAGCUCUUUACAGAAUACCAACGCAAGACCGCCCCCCCCACCCAACCCCUACCCAGGAUUGUAUUUACUAUGCUGAGAAUGCCUGGUAUCAGUUUCUCUCCUGAGAUCCUGGCCUCACUCUGAGCGCUGAUAGUAAUCUGACAUGUAACGCUUGGGGGAGGGAGAAACACUCUGUGACAAGCCGGCGGGUGGAAGGGCUGUGUGUGUCUCUGCCAGCUGUGUUUUGGGGACUGGUGCUCUCUGCUGAUUCUGUGGUUAAGCCUGCACACGUUUGCACACAUACAGGCACAGUGUGCAGGUGGAAAACUUACCCAAGAUGACAGAAGGUGCCCCCCGCCCCCAUUCCCAUUUAUUGUUCAAGGGACAGGUGAAUCUGAGCCUGUGACCGCAGCUGAGAAAUGUUGUGGACCCAGCUCAGGGUUCUCCCGGAGAGGCCUGGGGAGCUGGAAGCUCUGACCUCCGGGACAGGGGGUUGUAGAGGGGCCGAGGCCCAGGGUUGCACAGUGCCAAAAGGAUCCCGGUCAUUUUGACAGGAAGGGAGCUGUCGGGGAGGGAGCCGUUAGGUGCAGCUCCCCUUGUGGAGUCCAAGGGCCAGGUGGGUAGAAGUGCCCACCACUUGCAGGGUUGGCAGGGGAGCCCAGGGAGUGCACCAGUGUGCUGGGGGGUAGAUGUUGGGGGGUACAAGUGAGGGCCACUGGCCUCCCGACAGGGACAGGCAUGCUGCCCUGGAUGUCCUCAUGCUGCUUGUGACCGGCACAAAGGAAAAGAAUAUUGUUCUCGAUGCCAGCUUUGCUUGAUGACUUACCGAGCCUGCAGCUUGAGGAGGCAACUGACAGCCUGAGGAUGGGGCUCCUGGGCUGGUCAAGAUUUUUAAAGGUUUUGGGGCCUUGGUGGCUGGGUCUUGGCCACGGCUGGGUAACCUUUCCCGUGGAGAUGUAUGGGCAGAUAGUGAAGCUGCUCCGGAGAGUGGUAGGGUUGGCGGUCGAGUACAAAGGACUUGGACUAAGGACCGCGUUGUUCUCUUAGCAUCACAGUUGUUCUGAGCCAGGGCCUCUGGGAUCAUGUCCACGAGGAUGUGAGAUUGCCUUGUGCUGGCAUCUACACUAAGCGGAGUGGGCACCAGCUGUGUCCUCAGGACCAGGGCUUGAGGUGGGAGAUGGGGAGGGGGUGGGACAUGAGCCUUCUUGGCUGGCUUAGAGGGAUCCAGAAUUCCUAGAGGGCCUUUGUUGCAAAUCUCAGAGCCACCCAGGCUGAGAGCAAAUGCUUUGCUCGGCCUCCCAGCCCACCUCACAUCCGGCUACUCCCUCCAGGGCUGGCCUCCACUCCCCUCCUGGCCCUACCAGCUCUUGCCUGGAGCUCCACAUCAGCUACCUAGUAGGCUCCCCUUUCGUGGCCUUCCUAGCCCUUCUCCAGCCAGCAGCCAGCAUGGUGUUUAAAAAGAUAAACCACUUCAUGUAAUUUGACCACUUAGAGCCCUUUGAGAUUUGCCAUGGGUCUCAGUAAGUCCUGACCCCUUUCCAGACCCCACAGGCCCUAGAUGCCCCUCCACUCUGUCUCCCUUCCCUUGUUCUCCUCUCCCCCUCCCCUCCCCUCCCUCUCCCCUCCUUGCUCACAGGGGUCUGGCGUCAGCCCCGGCUUCUUACUCCAGGGCCUUUGCACUGCCUGUGCCUCUGCUUUCGGCCCCUCCUUGGAUCUGCAUUUGGUGGGCUCCAUCUAAUUCAGGUCCCAGCUCAGAUGCUGCCUCUCUGAGAGAGUCUCUGUUCCUGGCCCGUUACCCAUUCCAAAGCAGCUCUCAGCUCUGUGUUUUGUUUUCUCUUUAUUUAUACUGAAAUGGUCAUGUUUGUUUAAUUGAAUGGCUUCCUAUGGAGAAAGCGAUUGGGCCAAGCCAGGUUCAUGGUGGGCGCCGCUGGUGCGUGGCAUCUGUCCCUGGUGGGUGCCGCUGGUGCGCGGUGUCUGUCCCCAUGCACGGUUGCCUGCAAGUCUGCUCCGGGCUCUCUUCCCAGGGGCUGGCACACAGUAGGUGUUCUACGGUUAAGUGAGGCACAUGUGGAAAGCCGUCAUACUGUCUCAUCCCAGGGAGGUCAGUAGAUUGAGACUGGCUGCCCCCAUCUAGCAAGUCCCACCCACCAUGUCCUGGUUUCACCAGCAUCGGCUGGUGUGGGACGUGACCAGCUCAUUUCCUCCAUGCUCUAGGAUGGGAAGGACAAGAGGGCGUGACUCUUCCCAGAGUCCCAUCAUCUCUGAUUUAGGAAUGGAGCCCUUAGGGUGUCUCACCUCCUCGGGAUGCCUAAUAGUGUGUUUGGUGAAUGCAGAUGGACUUAACUGGUCCAUAGAUCCCCUCUCACCCUGCUGACACGAAGACAAGGAUGAAGGGGAAAGUUGAGGCUCAACAACUGAACAGUAUUCCUUCUAAAUAUGUACAUUCUUAGGGAUUUUAAGUGGAAAACAGGGAGGAGAUUUGAGGGAUACCCCACCUCGGCAGGCAGCUGGUCAGGCUGCCUGUUGUGACCAGCCUGGGGUCGCCUUCCCUUCAUCCAAGGCCAGGGGAGAUGGCAAACCUUCAGUAAGCGCUGCCGUACCUGGCAGAGCAGAAGCACCACCCCAGCUUGGAGACAGCAUGCCCCUGACUGCUGGUCACGGAUGGCCCCUUGAAGCCCCCGAGCGCCCACAGCAUGAAGGAGGAGGCCUUCCUCCGGCGCCGCUUCUCCCUGUGUCCACCUUCCUCCACCCCUCAGAAAGUCGACCCCCGGAAGCUCACCCGGAACUUGCUCCUCAGCGGAGACAAUGAGCUCUACCCACUCAGCCCAGGGAAGGACAUGGAGCCCAACGGCCCGUCGCUGCCCAGGGAUGAAGGGCCCCCGACCCCAAGCUCUGCCACGAAGGUGCCACCGGCAGAGUACAGGCUGUGCAACGGGUCAGACAAGGAAUGUGUGUCCCCCACCGCCAGGGUCACCAAGAAGGAGACUCUCAAGGCGCAGAAGGAGAACUACCGGCAGGAGAAGAAGCGCGCCACACGGCAGCUGCUCAGCGCUCUGACAGACCCCAGCGUGGUCAUCAUGGCUGACAGCCUGAAGAUCCGCGGCACCCUGAAGAGCUGGACCAAGCUGUGGUGCGUGCUGAAGCCGGGGGUGCUGCUCAUCUACAAGACGCCCAAGGUGGGCCAGUGGGUGGGCACGGUGCUGCUGCACUGCUGCGAGCUCAUCGAGCGGCCCUCCAAGAAGGACGGCUUCUGCUUCAAGCUCUUCCACCCGCUGGAUCAGUCCGUCUGGGCCGUGAAGGGCCCCAAAGGUGAGAGCGUGGGCUCCAUCACACAGCCCCUGCCCAGCAGCUACCUGAUCUUCAGGGCCGCCUCCGAGUCAGAUGGUCGCUGCUGGCUGGACGCCCUGGAGCUGGCCCUGCGCUGCUCUAGCCUACUGAGACUGGGCACCUGCAAGCCGGGCCGAGACGGGGAGCCAGGGACCUCGCCAGACGCAUCACCCUCAUCGCUCUGUGGGCUGCCAGCCUCAGCCACCGUCCACCCAGACCAAGACCUGUUCCCACUGAACGGGUCUUCCCUGGAGAACGAUGCAUUCUCAGACAAGUCGGAGAGAGAGAACCCUGAGGAGUCAGAUACCGAGACCCAGGACCAUAGCCGGAAGACGGAGAGUGGCAGCGACCAGUCAGAGACCCCUGGGGCCCCGGUGCGGAGAGGGACCACCUAUGUGGAGCAGGUCCAGGAGGAGCUGGGGGAGCUGGGCGAGGCGUCCCAGGUGGAGACAGUGUCAGAGGAGAACAAGAGUCUGAUGUGGACCCUGCUGAAGCAGCUACGGCCAGGCAUGGACCUGUCCCGCGUGGUGCUACCCACGUUCGUACUGGAGCCGCGCUCCUUCCUGAACAAGCUCUCCGACUACUACUACCACGCAGACCUGCUCUCCAGGGCUGCGGUGGAGGAGGAUGCCUACAGCCGCAUGAAGCUGGUGCUGCGGUGGUACCUGUCUGGCUUCUACAAGAAGCCCAAGGGAAUCAAGAAGCCGUACAACCCCAUCCUGGGGGAGACCUUCCGCUGCUGCUGGUUCCACCCGCAGACUGACAGCCGCACAUUCUACAUAGCAGAGCAGGUGUCCCACCACCCGCCCGUGUCUGCCUUCCACGUCAGCAACCGGAAGGACGGCUUCUGCAUCAGUGGCAGCAUCACAGCCAAGUCCAGGUUUUAUGGGAACUCGCUGUCGGCGCUGCUGGACGGCAAAGCCACGCUCACCUUCCUGAACCGAGCCGAGGAUUACACCCUUACCAUGCCCUACGCCCACUGCAAAGGAAUCCUGUAUGGCACGAUGACCCUGGAGCUGGGUGGGAAGGUCACCAUCGAGUGUGCGAAGAACAACUUCCAGGCCCAGCUGGAAUUCAAACUCAAGCCCUUCUUCGGGGGUAGCACCAGCAUCAACCAGAUCUCGGGAAAGAUCACGUCGGGAGAGGAAGUCCUGGCGAGCCUCAGUGGCCACUGGGACAGGGACGUGUUUAUCAAGGAGGAAGGGAGCGGAAGCAGUGCGCUUUUCUGGACCCCGAGCGGGGAGGUCCGCAGACAGAGGCUGAGGCAGCACACGGUGCCGCUGGAGGAGCAGACGGAGCUGGAGUCCGAGAGGCUCUGGCAGCACGUCACCAGGGCCAUCAGCAAGGGCGACCAGCACAGGGCCACACAGGAGAAGUUUGCACUGGAGGAGGCACAGCGGCAGCGGGCCCGUGAGCGGCAGGAGAGCCUCAUGCCCUGGAAGCCGCAGCUGUUCCACCUGGACCCCAUCACCCAGGAGUGGCACUACCGAUACGAGGACCACAGCCCCUGGGACCCCCUGAAGGACAUCGCCCAGUUUGAGCAAGACGGGAUCCUGCGGACCUUGCAGCAGGAGGCCGUGGCCCGCCAGACCACCUUCCUGGGCAGCCCAGGGCCCAGGCACGAGAGGUCUGGCCCAGACCAGCGGCUUCGCAAGGCCAGCGACCAGCCCUCCGGCCACAGCCAGGCCACGGAGAGCAGCGGAUCCACGCCUGAGUCCUGCCCAGAGCUCUCAGACGAGGAGCAGGAUGGUGACUUUGUCCCUGGCGGUGAGAGCCCAUGCCCUCGGUGCAGGAAGGAGGCGCGGCGGCUGCAGGCCCUGCACGAGGCCAUCCUCUCCAUCCGAGAGGCCCAGCAGGAGCUGCACAGGCACCUCUCGGCCAUGCUGAGCUCCACGGCACGGGCAGCACAGGCACCGACCCCAGGCCUCCUGCAGAGCCCCCGAUCCUGGUUCCUGCUCUGCGUGUUCCUGGCGUGUCAGCUGUUCAUUAACCACAUCCUCAAAUAGGAGCCCUGAGGGCAGAGCUCCUGGCCGGUCCUGAGCCCUCCCUCCCAGGCACCCAGCACUUUAAGCCUGCUCCAUGGAGGCAGAGAGGCCCGGCAAGCACAGCCACUGUGACGGGGAGUCCAGGCGCAGGAGGGACCCGGGGCCACAAGGCGCUGCGGGCCCAGGUGUGCUGGGCCCCUCUCAGGGGCACUGGCCUCUCUGCAGGGCCUUCCGCCCAGCGCUGGCCUUAAUGCUAAAGCCAAAUGCAGCUUCUGCUGUGCGACGCACUCCUGGCCAUCUUGCCGUGUCACCCCCUGUCCGGCCUCCACUUGCCAUGGGGGAUGGAUGGAUUUAGGGUGGGAGGGCCUGUGGGGGCCCUGGACAGUCACACCCCAGCAGCAGUGAGUGGGCAGGUUUGGAGGAGCCCCGAGUGGCCCAGGAGUCCCCCCACACACAGAUGCAUAGGCCUGCCUUCCGGAGACCCUGUCCACAUUGCCGGGACCACCCUGGUGGGGCCACUGGUGGGUGCCAGGGACAGGUUAGGGCCACUCUGGGGAAGGCAUUUUGGUUUUUUAUUCCACGCUGUGCUGUUUGGAUGGGAGCCCCACAGAGGCAGGUCCUGGAACCACCCCACCCCCACACCUGGACGCUCGCUCUGGUGGGGGCACACGCAGGUGGAGGUGGUUGUGGGUGCAGGUGUGUGCAGGGGUGUGGGGGGCGCAGGGGUGUGGCUUAGCUGGCCCCGCACCCAGGCCGGGGAGGCUCAAGUUCGCCACUUUACUCAGACCGAUGCACAGUCUUCCCAUUUUACACUUUUUUAAUAAACAUAAUUGCAAUAUUUUAGGUGGGCUGCGAGCUGCAGUCAGCCUUCACGUCUGGCCUCAGUCCCCGUGUCAGUGCCGCUCUGCGUGUGCGUGUGCGCGUGUGUGAGCCUCUACACAUAUAUAUACGUACAGAGCCUUAAACCACAUCGUGGCGGUGCCGUCUGAGCUGUAGCGGGUGGCUUUGUUUCCAGUUUUUGUACCCGUGUCCUUGUCUCCCCUCCUCCCCCAUCUGGGGAUGUGUCUGUGUUCCACACCUUGAAAUAAACAGACACAUACGUGUUCUCUUCUUGCGGGA